GCCACAGAGCAUCUUCAAGGAGCUGAACAAUGAGAACAAGAGCGCACUGCAGUUGGAGCAGCAAGUAAAGGAGCUACAGGAGAAGCUUGGUGAGGAGCACCUGGAAGCGGCCAGCCAGCAGAACCAGCAGCUAACGGCCCAGCUGAGCCUCAUGGCUCUCCCUGGGGAAGGACACGGAGGAGAACAUCUGGACAGUGACGGGGAGGAGGCACCUCGGCCCAUGCCGAGUGUCCCAGAGGACCUGGAGAGCAGGGAGGCCAUGAGCAGCUUUAUGGACCAACUGGAGGAGAAGGCAGACCUGAGUGAGCUGGUGAAGAAAAAAGAACUUUGCUUCAUCCACCACUGGCGAGAUAGAUGCCAUCAGAAAAUCCAUCACCUUUUAUCAGAACCAGGGGGCCGUGCCAAAGAUGCGGCACUGGUAGGAGGACACCAUCAGGCUGGAGCUCAGGGAGGAGAUGAAGGUGAAGCUGCUGGAGCUGCAGCAGAUGGUGUUGCGGCUUAUAGCAACUACAACAAUGGGCACAGAAAAUUCCUGGCCACUGCCCAGAACCCUGCUGAUGAGCCCGGUCCAGGAGCCCCAGCCCCCCAGGAGCUUGGGGCUGCAGGCAAGCAUGGUGGUUAUCUAUUUCAGAUACCUGUUUGCUCAUAUUUACAUUCCUAACUGAACAAUGUCUGAAGAGGUACUUAAACCUGUCAUAAAACACAAAUGAGCUUAUGACCAAAUGCUUAGUGCCAGAAAAAACUUCAAACUGCAAUAUGAGUCUCUCCAAAUACAGAAAGGACCAGUAUUUUAAGAGGUAUGUUAACUAAAAUGUUGCAGUGUAUGGAGCAGAGCAGGAAGAACCUUUAAGUCCGAAACUUACAAGUAAAUUUCAUAGUUUCCGUGGUCCUUCCACAACAACCUCUGGCAUCUGUUUUUUCUACAAUGGAGGUAACAGUAGCUCUUUCAGAGCAGGAAAAGGCUUAGAGCAGUGCUAGAAGAGGGUGGUGGCUAUAUAAAGUUUAGCUAUUUGUAUAUUGUAACAAACCACCUUUUUUUUUUUUUUAAGUCAGUAGUAGAUUUCUUUUGGAAAAGUAGCCGCCUCCUGUCUAGAGAUACCUGCAGUUCCACUAAGUGAACAUUGGUGUCUGCUCACCUUUGCCUCUAUUUCUCUCAAUAAUAUACUCUUAAGCUGUUCCCUGAUUUAGCAAUUUUAUACACUUUCUUUUUCUUUAUUUUUUUUUCCUUUCCCUUUUCCUGAGACACUGUCCCGCUCUGUCGC